AUGUGGCAGAAGAAUCAGACCUCUCUGGCAGACUUCAUCCUUGAGGGGCUCUUCGAUGACUCCCUUACCCACCUUUUCCUUUUCUCCUUGACCAUGGUGGUCUUCCUUAUUGCGGUGAGUGGCAACACCCUCACCAUUCUCCUCAUCUGCAUUGAUCCCCAGCUUCAUACACCAAUGUAUUUCCUGCUCAGCCAGCUCUCCCUCAUGGAUCUGAUGCAUGUCUCCACAAUCAUCCUGAAGAUGGCUACCAACUACCUAUCUGGCAAGAAAUCUAUCUCCUUUGUGGGCUGUGCAACCCAGCACUUCCUCUAUUUGUGUCUAGGUGGUGCUGAAUGUUUUCUCUUAGCUGUCAUGUCCUAUGACCGCUAUGUUGCCAUCUGUCAUCCACUGCGCUAUGCUGUGCUCAUGAACAAGAAGGUGGGACUGAUGAUGGCUGUCAUGUCAUGGUUGGGGGCAUCCGUGAACUCCCUAAUUCACAUGGCGAUCUUGAUGCACUUCCCUUUCUGUGGGCCUCGGAAAGUCUACCACUUCUACUGUGAGUUCCCAGCUGUUGUGAAGUUGGUAUGUGGCGACAUCACUGUGUAUGAGACCACAGUGUACAUCAGCAGCAUUCUCCUCCUCCUCCCCAUCUUCCUGAUUUCUACAUCCUAUGUCUUCAUCCUUCAAAGUGUCAUUCAGAUGCGCUCAUCUGGGAGCAAGAGAAAUGCCUUUGCCACUUGUGGCUCCCACCUCACGGUGGUUUCUCUUUGGUUUGGUGCCUGCAUCUUCUCCUACAUGAGACCCAGGUCCCAGUGCACUCUAUUGCAGAACAAAGUUGGUUCUGUGUUCUACAGCAUCAUUACGCCCACAUUGAAUUCUCUGAUUUAUACUCUCCGGAAUAAAGAUGUAGCUAAGGCUCUGAGAAGAGUGCUGAGGAGAGAUGUUAUCACCCAGUGCAUUCAACGACUGCAAUUGUGGUUGCCCCGAGUGUAG